GUUCUUGGAAGGCGGUGCUCUGAGAAGCCGGACUACGCGGCAGCGGCUCUUCAAAGCGGAGCCGGGAGUUUUUGCUACAGUUUUCGCCACCAUGAGUCGCAGCUAUAAUGAUGAGCUGCAGUUCUUGGAGAAGAUCAAUAAAAACUGCUGGAGGAUCAAGAAGGGCUUCGUGCCCAACAUGCAGGUUGAAGGUGUUUUCUAUGUGAAUGAUGCUCUGGAGAAAUUGAUGUUUGAGGAAUUAAGGAAUGCCUGUCGAGGUGGUGGUGUUGGUGGCUUCCUGCCAGCCAUGAAACAGAUUGGCAAUGUGGCAGCCCUGCCUGGAAUUGUUCAUCGAUCUAUUGGGCUUCCUGAUGUCCAUUCAGGAUAUGGGUUUGCUAUUGGGAACAUGGCAGCCUUUGAUAUGAAUGACCCUGAAGCAGUAGUAUCCCCAGGUGGUGUCGGGUUUGACAUCAACUGUGGUGUCCGCUUGCUAAGAACCAAUUUAGAUGAAAGUGAUGUCCAGCCUGUGAAGGAGCAACUUGCCCAAGCUAUGUUUGACCACAUUCCUGUUGGGGUGGGGUCAAAAGGUGUCAUCCCAAUGAAUGCCAAAGACUUGGAGGAGGCCUUGGAGAUGGGGGUGGACUGGUCCUUAAGAGAAGGGUAUGCCUGGGCUGAAGACAAGGAGCACUGCGAGGAGUACGGAAGGAUGCUGCAGGCUGACCCCAAUAAAGUUUCUGCAAGGGCGAAGAAAAGAGGCCUUCCUCAGUUGGGGACCCUGGGAGCAGGCAACCAUUAUGCAGAAAUCCAGGUUGUGGAUGAGAUUUUCAAUGAGUAUGCUGCUAAAAAAAUGGGCAUCGACCAUAAGGGACAGGUGUGUGUGAUGAUCCACAGUGGAAGCAGAGGCUUGGGCCACCAAGUAGCCACAGAUGCGCUGGUAGCUAUGGAGAAGGCCAUGAAGAGAGACAAGAUUAUAGUCAAUGAUCGGCAGUUGGCUUGUGCUCGAAUCGCUUCCCCAGAGGGUCAAGACUAUCUGAAGGGAAUGGCAGCUGCUGGGAACUAUGCCUGGGUCAACCGCUCUUCCAUGACCUUCUUAACCCGUCAGGCUUUCGCCAAGGUCUUCAACACAACCCCUGAUGACUUGGACCUACAUGUGAUCUAUGAUGUUUCUCACAACAUUGCCAAAGUGGAGCAGCAUGUGGUGGACGGAAAGGAACGGACACUGUUAGUACACAGGAAGGGAUCCACCCGCGCUUUCCCUCCUCACCAUCCCCUCAUUGCUGUUGAUUACCAACUCACUGGACAGCCAGUGCUCAUUGGUGGCACCAUGGGAACCUGUAGUUAUGUUCUUACUGGCACUGAACAGGGCAUGACUGAGACCUUUGGAACAACCUGUCAUGGAGCGGGCCGUGCAUUGUCCCGAGCAAAAUCUCGACGUAAUUUAGAUUUCCAGGAUGUCUUAGACAAAUUGGCAGAUAUGGGAAUUGCGAUCCGUGUUGCCUCACCCAAACUGGUUAUGGAAGAGGCUCCUGAGUCCUAUAAGAAUGUGACAGAUGUGGUAAAUACCUGCCAUGAUGCUGGAAUCAGCAAGAAAGCCAUUAAACUGAGACCAAUUGCUGUGAUCAAAGGAUAGAACCUUGGACAGCAGGGCUGCCUGACACCACCAACCCUCUCUGAAGUGGAAGUGGACUGACAUGCUCUUCUGACAUCAGACUCAAGGCGGGACAAGUUGCAAAGUGUGCAGCUGUAACUGCUCACGCCAAAAUGGCUGAUGGGGAGGCUGCUGCUUUCAGGGGCCCGUGCUUGUAAAAUAACCUUCCAGGAAGAGGCACAUUGCCCACCUUUGGAAAGGGAGGAAUAUGCCUUCUCCUUGGUUGUUCCACAGAGUUUUAGGAAAAUCUGUUAGGGAUGGGUAGAUGUCAAACUGCCUUACGCAGUCAUACUGAUCUUUAGCCAUCAGAUUGAUCUUCUUCACACCAAGCUCUGUUUACAUUCCGAGAGGUGUCAUGAAGAAAGUUCUGUUCAAUAAGGUUUUGGAAUGUU